ACGACAACUUCCGGAAGAGGUCGCCAUGGCUUCCCGGGAGGAGGUACUCGCCUUACAAGCUGAAGUUGCCCAACGUGAGGAGGAAUUGAAUUCGCUGAAGCAGAAGCUGGCGUCGGCUCUUUUGGCUGAGCAGGAACCGCAGCCAGAACGGCUGGUUCCGGUGUCGCCGCUGCCGCCGAAGGCCGCUCUGUCCCGAGAUGAGAUUCUGCGCUAUAGCCGGCAGCUAGUGCUGCCCGAGCUGGGCGUGCACGGACAGCUGCGCCUGGGGACCGCGUGCGUGCUAAUCGUGGGCUGCGGUGGGCUCGGCUGUCCACUAGCGCAGUACUUGGCAGCGGCCGGCGUGGGCCGCCUUGGCCUUGUGGACUAUGACGUGGUAGAGAUGAGCAACCUGGCCCGCCAAGUGCUGCAUGGCGAGGCACUGGCUGGCCAGGCCAAGGCCUUUUCGGCCGCCGCCUCGCUGCGCCGCCUCAAUUCGGCAGUGGAAUGCGUGCCGUACACUCAGGCCCUUACGCCAGCCACUGCCCUAGACCUGGUCCGCCGAUAUGAUGUGGUGGCUGACUGCUCGGACAACGUGCCCACUCGCUACCUGGUUAAUGACGCAUGUGUGCUGGCGGGUCGGCCCCUCGUGUCUGCCAGUGCCUUGCGCUUCGAGGGCCAAAUCACAGUCUACCAUUAUGACGGUGGCCCUUGCUAUCGCUGCAUAUUCCCCCAACCACCCCCAGCGGAGACAGUGACCAACUGCGCGGACGGCGGGGUGCUCGGUGUCGUUACCGGGGUCCUGGGCUGCCUGCAGGCCUUGGAAGUGCUGAAAAUCGCUGCGGGUCUGGGCCCCUCUUACAGUGGCAGCUUGUUGCUCUUUGAUGCCCUGAGAGGGCAUUUCCGCUCUAUUCGGCUGCGGAGCCGCAGGCUCGACUGUGCAGCUUGCGGGGAACGGCCCACUGUGACUGAUCUGCUGGACUAUGAAGCCUUCUGUGGCUCCUCAGCCACUGAUAAAUGCCGCUCCCUGCAACUACUGAGCCCAGAGGAGCGUGUUUCUGUCACCGACUAUAAGCGACUGCUGGAUUCUGGGGCAUUCCACCUGUUGCUGGACGUCAGGCCUCAGGUGGAGGUGGACAUUUGUCGUUUGCCUCAUGCCCUACACAUCCCUCUGAAACAUUUGGAACGCAGGGAUGCGGAGAGCCUGAAACUCUUAAAAGAAGCAAUCUGGGAAGAGAAGCAGGGCACACAAGAAGGGGCUGCUGUCCCCAUUUAUGUGAUUUGCAAACUGGGAAAUGACUCACAGAAAGCCGUGAAGAUCCUCCAGUCCUUAUCAGCAGCUCAAGAGUUAGACCCUUUAACAGUUCGGGAUGUUGUGGGGGGCCUCAUGGCCUGGGCUGCCAAAAUCGAUGGAACAUUUCCACAGUACUGAGGUGACUGGUAUAGUCUGAUGAGAAAGAUGUGGAUUGCCAUAAUACCUCAAAGAUACACUUGUUUGCAUUUUUCGGUAAUAUACAUAGGAGCUGGGGAUUCUACAGUAUCUGUGAAUACGUGGACUCCUUUUUAUAAGGAGUUUUAAAAAUUGUUAUGUAUUGGAUGAAUGACUUAUUAAUGGAUUAUACCGUUUCUGAGAACCAUCAUUUUUUUUUUCAGCACACGGAGGAUGUCUUGGACAUGUGAGAUGUAACGUGACAGGAUUUUGCAUUUUAAACUGCAGAUCAUUUACAUGUCCUUAUUUUCCACCUCCCCCAGUCAAAAUGCUUUCUAAAUCAUUUUCACAGAUUAUAUACUUCGGAUCUGUUUACUGUUCAGUUAAGAAAUUCUUGGAUCUUAUUAAUAUUUCAGAUGAUAGAAUACAUCCUACAGAAAUACAUGUUUAAAAUGUAAAUUGUUUUAAUUAUUCAGAAAGAGGGUCAUUCUAUUUGGCCUUUUGAAUUAGUAUCAAAAUGAGAUUUUUUUUUUUUUUUUGAGAUGGAAUCUCUCUCUGUUGCCCAGGCUGGAGUGUAGUGGUGCGAUCUCAGCUCACUGCAACCUCCGCCUCCCAGGUUCAAGCGAUUCUCCUGCCUCAGCCUCCUGAGUAGCUGGGAUUACAGGCGCACGCCACCACGCCUGGCUAAUUUUUGUAUUUUUAGUACAGAGGGGGUUUCACCAUGUUUGUCAGGCUGGUCUCGAACUCCUGACCUCGUGAUCCGCCUGCCUCGACUUCCCAGAGUGCUGGGAUUACAGGCGUGAGCCACCACACCCUCCCGAGAUCUUUAAAGUUUACCAAAAUAAAGGAAACCACCUUUGUAGUCUGUCAGUGUCUCUUAUAAAUUGCUACUGUUUUCUUAAAGUUAACUUCAGGGUCCACCUUAUGUUGCACACAUAUCACAUCGUUUAAAUUGCAUACUAUGGUUUGACUUGCUUUGGAAUUUUCAAGUCAAAGUCCCAACCCUUUGCCUCUCCCCCUUUAAUUUGCCUUUUCUCUUUUGAUUUAAUGUUUUUUUAUUCCAGCAUUUUAUACUAAUGUAAAAUGUUUUUAUGUUUGUUUACUUAACAUUUUCAUAAAAUAGUAGGUAGUCUCACCAACUUCCAAUAUAUACAACAACAUUAUAAGUAAAAAUUUGAUUUGUGAGUGCCUAUCAGUGGCCAGAUGAACUAAUGGCUUGUCAGAAGGGGGCCUGUGACCUCCUGCUUGCUGCAUGCAGGCUUAUAAUCAUCAAUUGCUGCUGUUGUUUUUUUAAGAAUGGCAGAAAUCACAGAUACAACUAUAAAAUCUUUGUAUUUCUGUUAACCAUUUUUUUUAAAGCUUAAAUGUAUCAUAAGCCAGCAAAAACCCUUUGUAGACCAGAUUUACUUACCAGUUUGCAAUUUGUGAUAUAGAAUCUUGUUUUAUUAUAAGAGGGUGGUAUUUAACAAAUUCAAAAUUAGUCAUCACUUUUUAACUGUGAAACAUUGUAACUAAUUCUUUGAACAGGUAUACUUAAAGUAUGGUAUACCCUUCUGUUAUAAAGAUGAAGCAGGUCUCUUAUGACUGUUCCUGCCAACGAGUUAUGGAGGUAAAUGACUGUGACCUGGAGUGGAGAACAAAGAUGGCUGGCCUGUGUUUUUCAUCUCCUUCUUCCAGGGACAACUGAUUCUGAUACAUAGCAGGAAACAAAUAGCGACACACAGGAACAAUUUCAUAUUCUAAAGACUGAAGUCCUAAAGUUAUAGACAGUUGUAGUUCCUAUAAACCUGGUUGUCACAGGGGACAGGCAAGAGAAGCUGACUAGCUAAGUGUUAAAAGGUUUACUAAAGUGAUAGGAGGUGCUUUUGAGAAUUUUGGGGACAGAUUCAAGGCUGUACUUCUAGGAAUGAUGCCCGAAAUCAUGCACAAAACUGGCCUUAGGAGAACAGUGUCUAUGUUGUGCUGCCCUAUCAAGUACCGGAGGAAACGCCACUACAGUCUCACCAGUUUCACUUGACGUGCCCCCCCAACUCUCCCAGAAAGCCCAACACUUCAGCCACAGUCCAUGUGUCGAGAAACAGAGUCACUACAUUAUUCUUUUCUGAGUCAAGCCUUAUGAGGGUGCCUGGUAGGCAGAGUCUAAUUACAUGCCUACAUCUUAGCUGCAAGAGAGGCUGGGAAUUUGUGUUUUGAUAUCUACAAUAGGAAGACAGAACUCAUGAUGUGGGAUUUUCCCAAAUAGUGAAAUAUUUUUCAAAAGAUGGGCUGUUAAGAAUAUAACAGAUACCCAGUACACAACCCAGAUCUAUUUCAGUAUUUGUUUUUUGUUGUUGUUGUUUUGGAGACAGAGUCUCGCUCUAUCCCCCAGGCUGGAUGGAGUGCAGCGGCACAAUCUCGGCUCACUGCAACCUCCACCUCCCAUGUUCAAGUGAUUCUCAUGCCUCAGCCUCCUGAGUAGCUGGGAUUACAGGCACCUGCCACCACAUCUGGCUAAUUUUUCUAUUUUUAGUAGCGAUGGGGUUUCGCCAUGUUGGCCUGGCUGGUCUUGAACUCCUGACCUCAGGUGAUCUGUGCACCUCAGCCUCCCAAAGUGCUAGGAUUACAGGCAUGAGUCACUGCACCUGGCAUAUAUUAGUAUUUGAAAUUUGGUUUUCUCUGGGGAUUGUAGCUAGGUUUUUAUGGUGAGAUAGGAUUUGAACAUAAUUUGUUUUUUGAGACGAAGUCUUGCUUCGUCGCCCAGGGUGGAGUGUAGUGUUGUGAUCACAGCUCGCUGUGGCCUCAACCUCCUGGGUUCAAGUGAUCCUCCCACCUCAGCCUCUCAAGUAGCUUGAAUUACAGUUGUAUGCCACCAUGCCUAGCCAUUUUUUAAUUUAAAAAUUUUUUGGUAGCAAUGGGGUCUGAAUAUGUGGCCUAGGCUGAUCUCAAACUCCUGGGCUCAAGCAUCCCUCCUGCCUCAGCCUCCCAAAGUGCUUGGGAUUACGGGUAUGAGGCACCAUGCCCAGCCUGAACUUGAUUUUUUUGUUGUUUCCUUUUCAUAACAAACAUCAAAUGCCUUCAGUGUACUAGUUCUUCUAGGUUCUGGAAUAAAAAUGAGCAAGAGGUUUCCUGUUGUAGAGGAGUUUAUAUUUAAAUGGUGAUAAGUAAAUUACUGAUAAGUGCCAUAAAAGAAAUGAAACUGUGACAUAUUAGGGUGGGGGAGGGGAUCUGUUUUGAAUAGCUUAAUUAUGGAAGGCCUCAGAGAUGACAUUAAACCCAAAACCUGAAAGGUGAGAAAGAGCCAGUUACAGAAGAUCUGAGGAAAAUUCUAUACUGGGAGAAAAAUAACUGUAAAGACCUCAAGGUAAAUAAACUUGGAAUGUUCCGUUCAAGAAACUGCAGAGGCAAGUUGGGUUGCAAACAAUUAGGGAGAGUGGGACAGGGUGAGGUUUGAGAAGCAGGGAACAUCAUAAACUUUGUAGACCAUAGUAGUUUGGUUUUUAUUCUAAAUACAAUAAUAGCUAAUAUUUUGAGCACUUACUGUGUUAUUUGGGAUUUGAAUCCAGAUGCUCUGGUUGAAGAGCCCAUUCCCUAAGUGUCAUGCUAUACUGACUCUAAGCAAAACUUUGCCAUUGCUUCAUAUGUGUUCAUGCCCUGUCAGGGCAUAGAAAGCAAUCUAUGUCCUGACAAUCACGGAAGUGUAUUCCAGAUACAAUAGAAAUGUACUCUGA